GGGGCGGGGGAGGAUCACGAGUUCGGGAGUUCGAGACCAGCCUGGCUAACAUAGUUGAAACCCCGUCUCCACUAAAAAUACAAAAAUUAGCCAGGUGUGGUGGCGCGCGCCUGUAGUCCCAGCUACUCUGGAGGCUAAGGAAGGAGAAUCGCUUGAAUCCGGGAGGCGGAAGUUGCAGUGAGCCGAGAUCGCACCACUGUACACCUGGGUGACAGAGUGAGACUCUGUCUCAAAAAAAAAAAAAAAGAAAAAAAGCCGGCCGGGUAUAGUGGCUCACGCCUGUAAUCCUAACACUUUGGGAGGCUGAGGUCGGGAGUUCGAGACCAGCCUGGCCAACAUGGAGAAACCCCGUCUCUACUAAAAAUACAAAAAAAAAAGGAGCCGGGGAUGGUGGCGCAUGCCUGUAAUCCCAGCUACUUGGGAGGCUGAGGCAGGAGAAUCGCUUGAACCUGGGAGGCGGAGGUUGCAGUGAGCCGAGAUCGCGCCAUUGCACUUCAGCCUGGGCAACAAGAACGAAACUCCGCCUCAAAAAAAAAAAAAAAAAAAAAAAAAAGCCGUGGGUCAGGAGCCAGAGCCCUCUGCUCUAGUCUUAGCUGUGCCAAUGUGACUCCCUGUGUGAUUUGGGGGUAAAUUACUGCCCCUCACUGGGUCUCUGUCUACCCACCUGCAAAAUGAGAGGAUCUUUGGAUGAGUCUCCUUAAUUCAUUUCCUGGACAAACUUCCUCCAAGGCUCCCCCAGAUUUACCAGUGACGCCCUUCCCUAAGUAUCAACUUAGCCGUACUUUGAACUCUGGCCCCUCAGGUUUCAAGGGGACGGCCUUGUCUGGGAUCAGCUCUGUCUGGGGAAAGAAGCUGCACCAGCCUCUGGAUAGCAGGCUGAGUCACUUGUUUCUUGUGCCUUGAGUCAGUUCUCUCAUCAGCUCUCCUCCUAGGCCAGUGUUAUUACCUCCAGUAAAGAUGGAAAAGUUGGGGUUCAGAGAGGGCUAGAGACAGACAGCCUGCUGUGUCCUGUCUUUUCUCCUGUGCUGUACAGGUUCACCAAUUUUUAAAAUCCAAAUAUAUCUCAUGGUACAGUGGAAGAACUGGCCAGAGAGUCUGGAAGUUUGGGUUCUGGUCCUGGCUGUGCCACUGACUCACUGUGACCUUGGGAUCUUGUGCUGUGAAGACAUUUCCCAAGUGCUUCAUGUUAGCCAGCAAAUCUGACCCACAAGGCCUGGAAAGAGGUGAUUGUUAGGUUGCGCAGAGGUGGUCUUAUCCAGCUCAGCUUCCCCUGGGACCCACCGUGGGACCUGAGGCAGAACUGGGGUGGACUUGGCCUCCUCCAUGGCACACCGGCUGCAGAUACGACUGCUGACGUGGGAUGUGAAGGACACGCUGCUCAGGCUCCGCCACCCCUUAGGGGAGGCCUAUGCCACCAAGGCCCGGGCCCAUGGGCUGGAGGUGGAGCCCUCAGCCCUGGAACAAGGCUUCAGGCAGGCAUACAGGGCUCAGAGCCACAGCUUCCCCAACUACGGCCUGAGCCACGGCCUAACCUCCCGCCAGUGGUGGCUGGAUGUGGUCCUGCAGACCUUCCACCUGGCGGGUGUCCAGGAUGCUCAGGCUGUAGCCCCCAUCGCUGAACAGCUUUAUAAAGACUUCAGCCACCCCUGCACCUGGCAGGUGUUGGAUGGGGCUGAGGACACCCUGAGGGAGUGCCGCACACGGGGUCUGAGACUGGCAGUGAUCUCCAACUUUGACCGACGGCUAGAGGGCAUCCUGGGGGGCCUUGGCCUGCGUGAACACUUCGACUUUGUGCUGACCUCCGAGGCUGCUGGCUGGCCCAAGCCGGACCCCCGCAUUUUCCAGGAGGCCUUGCGGCUUGCUCAUAUGGAACCAGUAGUGGCAGCCCAUGUUGGGGAUAAUUACCUCUGCGAUUACCAGGGGCCUCGGGCUGUGGGCAUGCACAGCUUCCUGGUGGUUGGCCCACAGGCACUGGACCCCGUGGUCAGGGAUUCUGUACCUAAAGAACACAUCCUCCCCUCUCUGGCCCAUCUCCUGCCUGCCCUUGACUGCCUAGAGGGCUCAACUCCAGGGCUUUGAGGCCAGUGAGGGAAGUGGCUGGGCCCUAGGCCAUGGAGAAAACCUUAAACAAACCCUGGAGACAGGGAGCCCCUUCUUUCUCCACAGCUCUGGACCUUUCCCCCUCUCCCUGCGGCCUUUGUCACCUACUGUGAUAAUAAAGCAGUGAGUGCUGAGCUCUCACCCUUCCCCCACUAA